GCCAGAGAGCUGGAAGUGAGAGCAGAUCCCUAACCAUGAGCACCAGCCAACCAGGGGCCUGCCCAUGCCAGGGAGCUGCAAGCCGCCCCGCCAUUCUCUACGCACUUCUGAGCUCCAGCCUCAAGGCUGUCCCCCGACCCCGUAGCCGCUGCCUAUGUAGGCAGCACCGGCCCGUCCAGCUAUGUGCACCUCAUCGCACCUGCCGGGAGGCCUUGGAUGUUCUGGCCAAGACAGUGGCCUUCCUCAGGAACCUGCCAUCCUUCUGGCAGCUGCCUCCCCAGGACCAGCGGCGGCUGCUGCAGGGUUGCUGGGGCCCCCUCUUCCUGCUUGGGUUGGCCCAAGAUGCUGUGACCUUUGAGGUGGCUGAGGCCCCGGUGCCCAGCAUACUCAAGAAGAUUCUGCUGGAGGAGCCCAGCAGCAGUGGAGGCAGUGGCCAACUGCCAGACAGACCCCAGCCCUCCCUGGCUGCGGUGCAGUGGCUUCAAUGCUGUCUGGAGUCCUUCUGGAGCCUGGAGCUUAGCCCCAAGGAAUAUGCCUGCCUGAAAGGGACCAUCCUCUUCAACCCCGAUAAAGAAACUGAAGCCCAGAGAUUAAGUGACUUGCCCAAGGUCACCCAGCUAAUAAGUGACAGUGCUGGGAUUCAUACCCAGGAAGCCUAAUUCUUAACCAUUACUCCACACUGCCUCUUCAUAAAUGGAUGGAUGAAUACAUUGAAAAUUGAUAAAUAAAUUACCUCCUCUAAAGGAGGAGGUAGUAGUGGGACCUCAAAGGCCGAGCAAAGGAGGCAGAGGGGUGUCUCUGAUGGCCCAGAUCUUGGGCCAGUCUUGUCCUUUGGUGGCUGGGAGUAGGGUGCUCACCAGCCCUCUUCUCCCUCUCUGCCCACAGAUGUGCCAGGCCUCCAAGCCGCCUCCCACAUUGGGCACCUGCAGCAGGAGGCUCACUGGGUGCUGUGUGAAGUCCUGGAACCCUGGUGCCCAGCAGCCCAAGGCCGCCUGACCCGUGUCCUCCUCACGGCCUCCACCCUCAAGUCCAUUCCGACCAGCCUGCUUGGGGACCUCUUCUUUCGCCCUAUCAUUGGAGAUGUUGACAUCGCUGGCCUUCUUGGGGACAUGCUUUUGCUCAGGUGACCUGUUCCAGCCCAGGCAGAGAUCAGGUGGGCAGAGGCUGGCAGUGCUGAUUCAGCCUGGCCAUCCCCAGAGGUGACCCAAUGCUCCUGGAGGGGGCAAGCCUGUAUAGACAGCACUUGGCUCCUUAGGAACAGCUCUUCACUCAGCCACACCCCACAUUGGACUUCCUUGGUUUGGACACAGUGUUCCAGCUGCCUGGGAGGCUUUUGGUGGUCCCCACAGCCUCUGGGCCAAGACUCCUGUCCCUUCUUGGGAUGAGAAUGAAAGCUUAGGCUGCUUAUUGGACCAGAAGUCCUAUCGACUUUAUACAGAACUGAAUUAAGUUAUUGAUUUUUGUAAUAAAAGGUAUGAAACAC